AGUUACUUUGGAGUGCAGAACCAUUUCAGACAUGCUGAGGGGGACUCUACUGUGCGCGGUGCUCGGGCUUCUGCGCGCCCAGCCCUUCCCCUGUCCGCCAGCUUGCAAGUGUGUCUUCCGGGACGCCGCGCAGUGCUCGGGGGGCGACGUGGCGCGCAUCUCCGCGCUAGGCCUGCCCACCAACCUCACGCACAUCCUGCUCUUCGGAAUGGGCCGCGGCGUCCUGCAGAGCCAGAGCUUCAGCGGCAUGACCGUCCUGCAGCGCCUCAUGAUCUCCGACAGCCACAUUUCCGCCGUUGCCCCCGGCACCUUCAGUGACCUGAUAAAACUGAAAACCCUGAGGCUGUCGCGCAACAAAAUCACGCAUCUUCCAGGUGCGCUGCUGGAUAAGAUGGUGCUCCUGGAGCAGUUGUUUUUGGACCACAAUGCGCUAAGGGGCAUUGACCAAAACAUGUUUCAGAAACUGGUUAACCUGCAGGAGCUCGCUCUGAACCAGAAUCAGCUCGAUUUCCUUCCUGCCAGUCUCUUCACGAAUCUGGAGAACCUGAAGUUGUUGGAUUUAUCGGGAAACAACCUGACCCACCUGCCCAAGGGGUUGCUUGGAGCACAGGCUAAGCUCGAGAGACUUCUGCUCCACUCGAACCGCCUUGUGUCUCUGGAUUCGGGGCUGUUGAACAGCCUGGGCGCCCUGACGGAGCUGCAGUUCCACCGAAAUCACAUCCGUUCCAUCGCACCCGGGGCCUUCGACCGGCUCCCAAACCUCAGUUCUUUGACGCUUUCGAGAAACCACCUUGCGUUUCUCCCCUCUGCGCUCUUUCUUCAUUCGCACAAUCUGACUCUGUUGACUCUGUUCGAGAACCCGCUGGCAGAGCUCCCGGGGGUGCUCUUCGGGGAGAUGGGGGGCCUGCAGGAGCUGUGGCUGAACCGCACCCAGCUGCGCACCCUGCCCGCCGCCGCCUUCCGCAACCUGAGCCGCCUGCGGUACUUAGGGGUGACUCUGAGCCCGCGGCUGAGCGCGCUUCCGCAGGGCGCCUUCCAGGGCCUUGGCGAGCUCCAGGUGCUCGCCCUGCACUCCAACGGCCUGACCGCCCUCCCCGACGGCUUGCUGCGCGGCCUCGGCAAGCUGCGCCAGGUGUCCCUGCGCCGCAACAGGCUGCGCGCCCUGCCCCGUGCCCUCUUCCGCAAUCUCAGCAGCCUGGAGAGCGUCCAGCUCGACCACAACCAGCUGGAGACCCUGCCUGGCGACGUGUUUGGGGCUCUGCCCCGGCUGACGGAGGUCCUGUUGGGGCACAACUCCUGGCGCUGCGACUGUGGCCUGGGGCCCUUCCUGGGGUGGCUGCGGCAGCACCUAGGCCUCGUGGGCGGGGAAGAGCCCCCACGGUGCGCAGGCCCUGGGGCGCACGCCGGCCUGCCGCUCUGGGCCCUGCCGGGGGGUGACGCGGAGUGCCCGGGCCCCCGGGGCCCGCCUCCCCGCCCCGCUGCGGACAGCUCCUCGGAAGCCCCUGUCCACCCAGCCUUGGCUCCCAACAGCUCAGAACCCUGGGUGUGGGCCCAGCCGGUGACCACGGGCAAAGGUCAAGAUCAUAGUCCGUUCUGGGGGUUUUAUUUUCUGCUUUUAGCUGUUCAGGCCAUGAUCACCGUGAUCAUCGUGUUUGCUAUGAUUAAAAUUGGCCAACUCUUUCGAAAAUUAAUCAGAGAGAGAGCCCUUGGGUAAACCAAUGGGAAAAUCUUCUAAUUACUUAGAACCUGACCAGAUGUGGCUCGGAGGGGAAUCCAGACCCGCUGCUGUCUUGCUCUCCCUCCCCUCCCCACUCCUCCUCUCUUCUUCCUCUUCUCUCUCACUGCCACGCCUUCCUUUCCCUCCUCCUCCCCCUCUCCGCUCUGUGCUCUUCAUUCUCACAGGCCCGCAACCCCUCCUCUCUGUGUCCCCCGCCCGUUCCUGGAAACUGAGCUUGACGUUUGUAAACUGUGGUUGCCUGCCUUCCCCAGCUCCCACGCGGGUGUGCGCUGACACUGCCGGGGGCGCUGGACUGUGUUGGACCCAUCCGUGCUCCGCUGUGCCUGGCUUGGCGUCUGGUGGAGAGAGGGGCCUCUUCAGUGUCUACUGAGUAAGGGGACAGCUCCAGGCCGGGGCCUGUCUCCUGCACAGAGUAAGCCGGUAAAUGUUUGUGAAAUCAAUGCGUGGAUAAAGGAACACAUGCCAUCCAAGUGAUGAUGGCUUUUCCUGGAGGGAAAGGAUAGGCUGUUGCUCUAUCUAAUUUUUUGUUUUUGUUUUUGGACAGUCUAGCUCUGUGGCCCAGGCUGGCGUGCAGUGGGCCGUCUCAGUUCACUGCAGCCUCCGCCUCCCAGGUUCAAGUGAUUCUCAUGCCUCAGCGUUCUGAGUAGCUGGGAUUAGAGGCGUGUGCCACUACACCCGGCUAAUUUUUGUACUUUUUAAAGUAGAGACGGGGCUUUGCCAUAUUGGCCUGGCUGAUCUCAAACUCCUGGUCUUGAACUCCUGGCCACAAGUGAUCUGCCCGCCUUGGCCUCCCAAAGUGCUGGGAUUACAGGCGUAAGCCACUACACCUGGCCCUCUUCAUCGAAUUUUAUUUGAGAAGUAGAGCUCUUGCCAUUUUUUCCCUUGCUCCAUUUUUCUCACUUUAUGUCUCUCUGACCUAUGGGCUACUUGGGAGAGCACUGGACUCCAUUCAUGCAUGAGCAUUUUCAGGAUAAGCGACUUCUGUGAGGCUGAGAGAGGAAGAAAACACGGAGCCUUCCCUCCAGGUGCCCAGUGUAGGUCCAGCGUGUUUCCUGAGCCUCCUGUGAGUUUCCACUUGCUUUACAUCCAUGCAACAUGUCAUUUUGAAACUGGAUUGAUUUGCAUUUCCUGGAACUCUGCCACCUCAUUUCACAAGCAUUUAUGGAGCAGUUAACAUGUGACUGGUAUUCAUGAAUAUAAUGAUAAGCUUGAUUCUAGUUCAGCUGCUGUCACAGUCUCAUUUGUUCUUCCAACUGAAAGCCGUAAAACCUUUGUUGCUUUAAUUGAAUGUCUGUGCUUAUGAGAGGCAGUGGUUAAAACAGGGGCUGGCGAGUUGACAACUGUGGGUUCAAAUCCCAGCUCUACCACUUACUAACUGCAUGGGACUUUGGGUAAGACACCUGCUUACAUUCUCUAAGCCUUGGUUUCCUGAACCUUAAAACAGGAUAACAUAGUACCUGCUUCGUAGAGUUUUUGUGAGAAUUAAAGGCAAUAAAGCAUAUAAUGACUUAGCCCAGCGGCCUGCAGGCAAUACAUGUUAAUGAAUGUUAGCUAUUAUUACUAAAGGAUGAGCAAUUAUUAUUGGCAUCAUGAUUUCUAAAGAAGAGCUUUGAGUUGGUAUUUUUCUCUGUGUAUAAGGGUAAGUCCGAACUUUCUCAGACUGGAGGUUACAUUCACAUCAGUCUGUCUUCCCCUGCGGAUGGCCUCAGCCCUGGGUGGCCAGACUCUGUGCUCACAAUCCAGAGCAAUGGAUCC